CGACCAUUGCUCUCCUGGCUGAGGAUGGCAACCUAGUGAGCCUGGAGGAGGACCUGAAGGAAGGGGCUUCCCGGGCCCAGACCAUGGGCAACUCCCUACUGAAGGAGCGAGCCAUAUAUGUCCUCGUUCGGAUCAUCAGUAAGAGGGAGAGGACAUGGCCUCCACCCGCUAUGAGUCCCUAUUGGAGAACCUGGAUGACCAUUACCCAGAGCUGGCAGAGGAACUGCGCAGGCUGUCAGGCCUCUCCUCUGUGGGCCACAACUGGAGGAAGCGUAUGGGCACUCGGCGAGGCCGCCAUGAGCAAAGCCCCACUUCAAGGCCCAGAAAGGGCCCUGAUUAAGGGGAUGGAUUGCACACUGUAGUGAGACAUCCAUCCUGACCCCACCUCAUCAGCCAGGGAGCUCCCUGAAGACAGGCCAUCGAGAGAGGCACACAACAGGCUGUGGUCUAAAAUAAACUUUUAAUUGCACA